GGGCUCCCCGCGCCGCCCGGUCGGCAGCAGGGCGCUGAGCGAGCUCGGAGCCCGCGCUGUGCGCCUGCGGCCGGGGCGCCCCGCCGAGCGCCGGUGCCCCGGCUCCCGGGCCGCCUUCGCCGCGCGGGAAGGAUUCUUCAAAAUUAACAGAAACCAAUUCGGGCCAGCUGAAGAGAAAAAAUAAAGCAUUUCUUCCUUCUGAUGGGGCAAGACUCUCUCUGGAAUGGGGCUCUUAUGACCUACAGUCAAACAAGGUGGCUCCCGGCUGCCUCUGCUGCAGUUCAGAGCAACUUCAGGAGCUUCCCAGCCGAGAGCUUCAGGACGCCUUUCCUGUCCCACUGGCCCAGUUGCCACAACAAACAACAGAGAAGACGGUGGUGCCCAGAAGAGACUGCUGCCCCCAAGGUGAGAUGGCACCUGGCCAGCUGCCCAAGCAGACCAUGGGGGAUGUGAAGCUGGUUGCCUCGUCACACAUUUCCAAAACCUCCCUCAGUGUGGAUCCCUCAAGAGUUGACUCCAUGCCCCUGACAGAGGCCCCUGCUUUCAUUUUGCCCCCUCGGAACCUCUGCAUCAAAGAAGGAGCCACCGCCAAGUUCGAAGGGCGGGUCCGGGGUUACCCAGAGCCCCAGGUGACAUGGCACAGAAACGGGCAACCCAUCACCAGCGGGGGCCGCUUCCUGCUGGAUUGCGGCAUCCGGGGGACUUUCAGCCUUGUGAUUCAUGCUGUCCAUGAGGAGGACAGGGGAAAGUAUACCUGUGAAGCCACCAAUGGCAGUGGUGCUCGCCAGGUGACAGUGGAGUUGACAGUAGAAGGAAGUUUUGCGAAGCAGCUUGGUCAGCCUGUUGUUUCCAAAACCUUAGGGGAUAGAUUUUCAGCUCCAGCAGUGGAGACCCGUCCUAGCAUCUGGGGGGAGUGCCCACCAAAGUUUGCUACCAAGCUGGGCCGAGUUGUGGUCAAAGAAGGACAGAUGGGACGAUUCUCCUGCAAGAUCACUGGCCGGCCCCAACCGCAGGUCACCUGGCUCAAGGGAAAUGUUCCACUGCAGCCGAGUGCCCGUGUGUCUGUGUCUGAGAAGAACGGCAUGCAGGUUCUGGAAAUCCAUGGAGUCAACCAAGAUGACGUGGGAGUGUACACGUGCCUGGUGGUGAACGGGUCGGGGAAGGCCUCGAUGUCAGCUGAACUUUCCAUCCAAGGUUUGGACAGUGCCAAUAGGUCAUUUGUGAGAGAAACAAAAGCCACCAAUUCAGAUGUCAGGAAAGAGGUGACCAAUGUAAUCUCAAAGGAGUCGAAGCUGGACAGUCUGGAGGCUGCAGCCAAAAGCAAGAACUGCUCCAGCCCCCAGAGAGGUGGCUCCCCACCCUGGGCUGCAAACAGCCAGCCUCAGCCCCCAAGGGAGUCCAAGCUGGAGUCAUGCAAGGACUCGCCCAGAACGGCCCCGCAGACCCCGGUCCUUCAGAAGACUUCCAGCUCCAUCACCCUGCAGGCCGCAAGAGUUCAGCCGGAACCAAGAGCACCAGGCCUGGGGGUCCUAUCACCUUCUGGAGAAGAGAGGAAGAGGCCAGCUCCUCCCCGUCCAGCCACCUUCCCCACCAGGCAGCCUGGCCUGGGGAGCCAAGAUGUUGUGAGCAAGGCUGCUAACAGGAGAAUCCCCAUGGAGGGCCAGAGGGAUUCAGCAUUCCCCAAAUUUGAGAGCAAGCCCCAAAGCCAGGAGGUCAAGGAAAAUCAAACUGUCAAGUUCAGAUGUGAAGUUUCCGGGAUUCCAAAGCCUGAAGUGGCCUGGUUCCUGGAAGGCACCCCCGUGAGGAGACAGGAAGGCAGCAUUGAGGUUUAUGAAGAUGCUGGCUCCCAUUACCUCUGCCUGCUGAAAGCCCGGACCAGGGACAGUGGGACAUACAGCUGCACUGCUUCCAACGCCCAAGGCCAGCUGUCCUGUAGCUGGACCCUCCAAGUGGAAAGGCUUGCCGUGAUGGAGGUGGCCCCCUCCUUCUCCAGUGUCCUGAAGGACUGCGCUGUUAUUGAGGGCCAGGAUUUUGUGCUGCAGUGCUCCGUACGGGGGACCCCAGUGCCCCGGAUCACUUGGCUGCUGAAUGGGCAGCCCAUCCAGUACGCUCGCUCCACCUGCGAGGCCGGCGUGGCUGAGCUCCACAUCCAGGAUGCCCUGCCGGAGGACCAUGGCACCUACACCUGCCUAGCUGAGAAUGCCUUGGGGCAGGUGUCCUGCAGCGCCUGGGUCACCGUCCAUGAAAAGAAGAGUAGCAGGAAGAGUGAGUACCUUCUGCCUGUGGCUCCCAGCAAGCCCACUGCACCCAUCUUCCUGCAGGGCCUCUCUGAUCUCAAAGUCAUGGAUGGAAGCCAGGUCACUAUGACUGUCCAAGUGUCAGGGAAUCCACCCCCUGAAGUCAUCUGGCUGCACAAUGGGAAUGAGAUCCAAGAGUCAGAGGACUUCCACUUUGAACAGAGAGGAACUCAGCACAGCCUUUGUAUCCAGGAAGUGUUCCCGGAGGACACGGGCACGUACACCUGCGAGGCCUGGAACAGCGCUGGAGAGGUCCGCACCCAGGCCGUGCUCACGGUACAAGAGCCUCACGAUGGCACCCAGCCCUGGUUCAUCAGUAAGCCUCGCUCAGUGACAGCCUCCCUGGGCCAGAGUGUCCUCAUCUCCUGCGCCAUAGCUGGUGACCCCUUUCCUACCGUGCACUGGCUCAGAGAUGGCAAAGCCCUCUGCAAAGACACUGGCCACUUCGAGGUGCUUCAGAAUGAGGACGUGUUCACCCUGGUUCUAAAGAAGGUGCAGCCCUGGCAUGCCGGCCAGUAUGAGAUCCUGCUCAAGAACCGGGUUGGCGAAUGCAGUUGCCAGGUGUCACUGAUGCUACAGAACAGCUCUGCCAGAGCCCUUCCACGGGGGAGGGAGCCUGCCAGCUGCGAGGACCUCUGUGGUGGAGGAGUUGGUGCUGAUGGUGGUGGUAGUGACCGCUAUGGGUCCCUGAGGCCUGGCUGGCCAGCAAGAGGGCAGGGUUGGCUAGAGGAGGAAGACGGCGAGGACGUGCGAGGGGUGCUGAAGAGGCGCGUGGAGACGAGGCAGCACACUGAGGAGGCGAUCCGCCAGCAGGAGGUGGAGCAGCUGGACUUCCGAGACCUCCUGGGGAAGAAGGUGAGUACAAAGACCCUAUCGGAAGACGACCUGAAGGAGAUCCCAGCCGAGCAGAUGGAUUUCCGUGCCAACCUGCAGCGGCAAGUGAAGCCAAAGACUGUGUCUGAGGAAGAGAGGAAGGUGCACAGCCCCCAGCAGGUCGAUUUUCGCUCUGUCCUGGCCAAGAAGGGGACUUCCAAGACCCCCGUGCCUGAGAAGGUGCCACCGCCAAAACCUGCCACCCCGGAUUUUCGCUCAGUGCUGGGUGGCAAGAAGAAAUUACCAGCAGAGAAUGGCAGCAGCAGUGCCGAGACCCUGAAUGCCAAGGCAGUGGAGAGUUCCAAGCCCCUGAGCAAUGCACAGCCUUCAGGGCCCUUGAAACCCGUGGGCAACGCCAAGCCUGCUGAGACCCUGAAGCCAAUGGGCAACGCCAAGCCUGCCGAGACCCUGAAGCCCAUGGGCAAUGCCAAGCCUGAUGAGAACCUGAAAUCCGCUAGCAAAGAAGAACUCAAGAAAGACGUUAAGAAUGAUGUGAACUGCAAGAGAGGCCAUGCAGGGACCACAGAUAAUGAAAAGAGAUCAGAGAGCCAGGGGACAGCCCCAGCCUUCAAGCAGAAGCUGCAAGAUGUUCAUGUGGCAGAGGGCAAGAAGCUGCUGCUCCAGUGCCAGGUGUCUUCUGACCCCCCAGCCACCAUCAUCUGGACGCUGAACGGAAAGACCCUCAAGACCACCAAGUUCAUCAUCCUCUCCCAGGAAGGCUCACUCUGCUCCGUCUCCAUCGAGAAGGCACUGCCUGAGGACAGAGGCUUAUACAAGUGUGUAGCCAAGAAUGACGCUGGCCAGGCGGAGUGCUCCUGCCAAGUCACCGUGGAUGAUGCUCCAGCCAGUGAGAACACCAAGGCCCCAGAGAUGAAAUCCCGGAGGCCCAAGAGCUCUCUUCCUCCCGUGCUAGGAACUGAGAGUGAUGCGACUGUGAAAAAGAAACCUGCCCCCAAGACACCUCCGAAGGCAGCAAUGCCCCCUCAGAUCAUCCAGUUCCCUGAGGACCAGAAGGUACGCGCAGGAGAGUCAGUGGAGCUGUUUGGCAAAGUGACAGGCACUCAGCCCAUCACCUGUACCUGGAUGAAGUUCCGAAAGCAGAUCCAGGAAAGCGAGCACAUGAAGGUGGAGAACAGCGAGAAUGGCAGCAAGCUCACCAUCCUGGCCGCGCGCCAGGAGCACUGCGGCUGCUACACACUGCUGGUGGAGAACAAGCUGGGCAGCAGGCAGGCCCAGGUCAACCUCACUGUCGUGGAUAAGCCAGACCCCCCAGCUGGCACACCUUGUGCCUCUGACAUUCGGAGCUCCUCACUGACCCUGUCCUGGUAUGGCUCCUCAUAUGAUGGGGGCAGUGCUGUACAGUCCUACAGCAUCGAGAUCUGGGACUCAGCCAACAAGACGUGGAAGGAACUAGCCACAUGCCGCAGCACCUCUUUCAACGUCCAGGACCUGCUGCCUGACCACGAAUAUAAGUUCCGUGUACGUGCAAUCAACGUGUAUGGAACCAGUGAGCCAAGCCAGGAGUCUGAACUCACAACGGUAGGAGAGAAACCUGAAGAGCCGAAGGAUGAAGUGGAGGUGUCAGAUGAUGAUGAGAAGGAGCCCGAGGUUGAUUACCGGACAGUGACAAUCAAUACUGAACAAAAAGUAUCUGACUUCUACGACAUUGAGGAGAGAUUAGGAUCUGGGAAAUUUGGACAGGUCUUUCGACUUGUAGAAAAGAAAACUCGAAAAGUCUGGGCAGGGAAGUUCUUCAAGGCAUAUUCAGCAAAAGAGAAAGAGAAUAUCCGGCAGGAGAUUAGCAUCAUGAACUGCCUCCACCACCCUAAGCUGGUCCAGUGUGUGGAUGCCUUUGAAGAAAAGGCCAACAUCGUCAUGGUCCUGGAGAUCGUGUCAGGAGGGGAGCUGUUUGAGCGCAUCAUUGACGAGGACUUUGAGCUGACGGAGCGUGAGUGCAUCAAGUACAUGCGGCAGAUCUCGGAGGGAGUGGAGUACAUCCACAAGCAGGGCAUCGUGCACCUGGACCUCAAGCCGGAGAACAUCAUGUGUGUCAACAAGACGGGCACCAGGAUCAAGCUCAUCGACUUUGGUCUGGCCAGGAGGCUGGAGAAUGCGGGGUCUCUGAAGGUCCUCUUUGGCACCCCAGAAUUUGUGGCUCCUGAAGUGAUCAACUAUGAGCCCAUCGGCUACGCCACAGACAUGUGGAGCAUCGGGGUCAUCUGCUACAUCCUAGUCAGUGGCCUUUCCCCCUUCAUGGGAGACAACGAUAACGAAACCUUGGCCAACGUUACCUCAGCCACCUGGGACUUCGACGACGAGGCAUUCGAUGAGAUCUCCGACGAUGCCAAGGAUUUCAUCAGCAAUCUGCUGAAGAAAGAUAUGAAAAACCGCCUGGACUGCACGCAGUGCCUUCAGCAUCCAUGGCUAAUGAAAGAUACCAAGAACAUGGAGGCCAAGAAACUCUCCAAGGACCGGAUGAAGAAGUACAUGGCAAGAAGGAAAUGGCAGAAAACGGGCAAUGCUGUGAGAGCCAUUGGAAGACUGUCCUCUAUGGCAAUGAUCUCAGGGCUCAGUGGCAGGAAAUCCUCAACAGGGUCACCAACCAGCCCGCUCAAUGCAGAAAAACUAGAAUCUGAAGAAGAUGUGUCCCAAGCUUUCCUUGAGGCUGUUGCUGAGGAAAAGCCUCAUGUAAAACCCUAUUUCUCUAAGACCAUUCGCGAUUUAGAAGUUGUGGAGGGAAGUGCUGCUAGAUUUGACUGCAAGAUUGAAGGAUACCCAGACCCCGAGGUUGUCUGGUUCAAAGAUGACCAGUCAAUCAGGGAGUCCCGCCACUUCCAGAUAGACUACGAUGAGGACGGGAACUGCUCUUUAAUUAUUAGUGAUGUUUGCGGGGAUGACGAUGCCAAGUACACCUGCAAGGCUGUCAACAGUCUUGGAGAAGCCACCUGCACAGCAGAGCUCAUUGUGGAAACGAUGGAGGAAGGUGAAGGGGAAGGGGAAGAGGAAGAAGAGUGAAACAAAGCCAGAGAAAAGCAGUUUCUAAGUCAUAUUAAAAGGACUAUUUCUCUAAAACUCAAAAAAAAAAAAAAAACUCAAGAUAGUAAAAGCACCUAGUGUGAUAGAUUAUCGGUUAGGUCAUUUGUGGGUUGAUUCUUCAGAAACAGCAGUUGAUACCUAGCAGCGUUAUUGAUGGGCAUUAAUCUAUGUUAGUUGGCACCUUAAGAUACUAGUGCAGCUAGAUUUCAUUUAGGGAAAUCACCAGUAACUUGACUGACCAAUUGAUUUUAGAGAGAAAGUAACCAAACCAAAUAUUUAUCUGGGCAAAGUCAUAAAUUCUCCACUUGAAUGCGCUCAUGAAAAAUAAGGCCAAAACAAGAGUUCUGGGCCACAGCUCAGCCCAGAGGGUUCCUGGGGAUGGGAGGCCUCUCUCUCCCCACCCCCUGACUCUAGAGAACUGGGUUUUCUCCCAGUACUCCAGCAAUUCAUUUCUGAAAGCAGUUGAGCCACUUUAUUCCAAAGUACACUGCAGAUGUUCAAACUCUCCAUUUCUCUUUCCCCUUCCACCUGCCAGUUUUGCUGACUCUCAACUUGUCAUGAGUGUAAGCAUUAAGGACAUUAUGCUUCUUCGAUUCUGAAGACAGGUCCCUGCUCAUGGAUGACUCUGGCUUCCUUAGGAAAAUAUUUUUCUUCCAAAAUCAGUAGGAAAUCUAAACUUAUCCCCUCUUUGCAGAUGUCUAGCAGCUUCAGACAUUUGGUUAAGAACCCAUGGGAAAAAAAAAAUCCUUGCUAAUGUGGUUUCCUUUGUAAACCAGGAUUCUUAUUUGUGCUGUUAUAGAAUAUCAGCUCUGAACGUGUGGUAAAGAUUUUUGUGUUUGAAUAUAGGAGAAAUCAGUUUGCUGAAAAGUUAGUCUUAAUUAUCUAUUGGCCACGAUGAAACAGAUUUCAACUGAUAAAGAGCUGGAGAACUCCAUGUACUUUGGAAUCUCCUCCAAGAUAGCCAGAGUUUAAUACAUCUUCAUUCUCAACACUCUCCAAAGAACUUGACCUACCUUAUGGGUUCCAUAUUUUUCUUCUUAAAUGUGCAUCAAUCAUGCCUUGCCCCCAACCUUUAAAUAUAUUCUUAGACCUGGUAAAUGCACUCAGACUUGCGUCUUUAGGAAUUUUUAACUUUCUUUCACUACAUUGGCACUUAAAUUUUUUCUUUAUAAAGCUUUUUGAAGGUCAUAAACAAAGACCAUAAUUGAUGAUAGACCUAAUACAUUUCCUCUGUGUGUGUGUGUAACAUUCCAAAUACUUUUUUUUUCUUUUCCACUGUUUGUAAGGUGCAACAAUUUAAUAUUUUUAAGGGACUUUUUAAGAGUUCCUUAAGAACCAAUUUAAAAUUACUUCAGUGCAAUCCUACACAGUAUCAACAUUAGAAUUUUGAUAUUAGUCUUAUGUUAUCUUCCAUUCUAUUUUUAUCUGCUUUUUGCUGCUAGUUUCAAACUGCCAGUAUUUUUCCUUUUGCUUUUAAAAUAGUUACAAUAUUUUUCAUGAUAGCCACAGUAUUGCCACAGUUUAUUAUAAUAAAGGGUUUUUAUUUGAUUUAGCGCAUUCAAAGCUUUUUUCUAUCACUUUUGUGUUCAGAAUAUAACCUUUGUGUGCGUGUAUGUUGUGUGUGUGCAUGUGUGGCGUAUAUGUGUGUUACAGGUUAAUGCCUUCUUGGAAUUGUGUUAAUGUUCUCUUGGUUUAUUAUGCCAUCAGAAUGGUAAAUGAGAACACUACAACUGUAGUCAGCUCACAAUUUUUAAAUAAAGGAUACCACAGUGCAUGCUGUUUGUUCAAUCUUUGCAGACUUCUCUUUCUUUCCAUGCUACCAGUUGUAAAGGACACAGCUAUAUCCUGGAAAUGAAAAACAAACACUGUGGUGCCUAGAUGUGAAGAACUGGCUUAUGUGGUUGUGUUUUGCUAUGGAACAGAAUGAUUUAGGAAGUUCUUGUUUAUAUAGGUAGCCGAAUUUACACAUUUAGUUCAAAAUUUCUCUUGAGCAUCAGCUUAGUACUAUAUCAAUCAUUCUAGAAGGAUAUCUUAUAGAGCAGGUGUCCCCAACCCCCGGUAAGUAGCCUGUUAGGAACCAGGUCACACAUAAGGAGGUUAGCAGUGGGCAAGUGAGCAAAGCAUCAUCUAUAUUUACAGCCGAUCCCCAUUGCUCGCAUUACCGCCUGAGCUCUGCCUCCUGUCAGAUCAGCGGCAGCAUCAGGUUCUCUCAGGAACGAACUCUAUUGUGAACUGCUCAUGUGAGGGAUCUAGGUUUCACGCUCCUUAUGAGAAUCUAACACCUGAUGAUCUGUCACUGUCUCCCAUCACCCCUAGAUGGGACAGUCUAGUUGCAGGAAAACAAGCUCAGGGCUUCCACUGAUUCUACAUUAUGAUGAGUUGUAUACUUAUUUUAUAUUAUAAUAAAAUAUAUUAUUACAAUGUAAUAAUAAUAGAAAUAAAAUGCACAAUACAUGUAAUGUGCUUGAAUAAUCCCAAAACCACCCCCUCUCCUGGUCCAUGGAAAAACUGUCUUCCAUGAAAGUGGUCCCUGGUGCCAAAAAGGUUAGGGACCACUGUUACAGAGUAUCAGGUCCUCAAGAUGCUAAAAUCUAUAUGACAUUUUUAACAUGUGACAUUAUCAUCAUCAUCAUCAUCAUCAUCACUGAUGAUACUAUUUACCAGGGCAUGGUUUGAAUUGGUGACUUUGGUGCAGUUCAUUAUUGGCAGCCAAAUGCUUUAUCCAUACCUUCAUAUUGAAGAAUUUGUUAUCAGGAAACUACCAGUCCUGCUUUACAGGAAGUCUGUUAUCAGAUAUCAGAUGGCAAGUUCCCCAUGUCUUCAGAUGUUCAAACAAUAUUGUGGAUGGUCUAGAAAGAGUUUAAGACAUGCUGUUAAAUGUAGGGCUAGAUAAUUCUCUGAUUCUUUGAUGUAGUCUGGAAAGAAACAAUCCAUUGUCCAGUUAAUAAAUAUUUAGUGUUUUCAUUUUUAAGACACUCACAAUCCACAAAUGUCCCUAACAAUUUAUUAUUUUUAAAGAAAAUGACUUUUUAUUCCUUGCUAGUGAAAAAUGUACAAUUUAUAUGCUGCACUGAGAAAAAUAACAGAUAUACUUUCUUCCAUUCAUUUUCAUCCCAAACAUAUAAAAAAUAAUCCAUUGAUUGUUCCUUGCAUUGCAUAUCUUAUUAAAAGAUAUUUCCUACAUGCAACUAAUAAGACAUGCUGACUGUUGUCAGCUCUAAAUUUAUGUAAAGAUUUUUUAUUUUUGUUAAAAUGUUUGAAAUUUGCUUUUUGCUCCACACCUCACCUGUUUUUGAUAAAUCUGUGCUAAUAAGUACAUAGGAGGUAAUAAAUAAUUGAGUUGUGAGAAACCCAAUUCUCCAUUUUUCAAGAAAACACAAGUAGCACUACUCUCUUUAUCCCUUGGGACUCCUUCCUGUAAUUUGAAAGGGGGGGCUAAUGUUGGUGGCAGUUGUUGCUAAGGAUCUCUGCACAGAGUUAGGGCUUCACUCUCGGCUUCCUGGUUAGAUGGGGCCAUGUGACUAGUCCUAGUCAGUGAGCUGUGACCAGAAGUGAUGUAUGUACCCUCGGGACCAGAGCAUUUAUGUGCUGGUACAAGCCUCUCCAUAAUGACGGGCAACACAUGAGAUGGUGGCUGCUGCAGCCAUCUGGGUCUCUAGCCAACCCAAAAUGGGGACAUAACACAAGCAAGAAAUAAACAUUUGUUCUUAUAAAUCACCAAGAUUUUGGGGUUCUCAGUGGCUGCAACAUAACCUAGACUAUCCUGAUACAGGCUUAUCACCAUGUUCUGGAUGUGUGGUGACCAGGAUGGUAGCCACUACUCACAAGUGGCUAUUUAAAUUUAAGUUACUUUAAAAAAUAAAAUAAAAAAUUCAGUUCCUCAGUUGUAUGAGUUACAUUUCAAAUGCUCGACAGUCACAUGUACAUCACUUUUCAAAUUAUGUGAAAUUAAAACUGAAAAGCUUGUGUGAAAGUCUAGAGAGUAUGGUCUAUAGUUUCAUCAAUUGUAUUGGAUAAUAUAGUCUCGAUACUCAA